GCAGUUAGAGCCGAUCUCCCGCGCCCCGAGGUUGCUCCUCUCCGAGGUCUCCCGCGGCCCAAGUUCUCCGCGCCCCGAGGUCUCCGCGCCCCGAGGUCUCCGCGGCCCGAGGUCUCCGCCCGCACCAUGCGGCUGGGCAGUCCUGGACUGCUCUUCCUGCUCUUCAGCAGCCUUCGAGCUGAUACUCAGGAGAAGGAAGUCAGAGCGAUGGUAGGCAGCGACGUGGAGCUCAGCUGCGCUUGCCCUGAAGGAAGCCGUUUUGAUUUAAAUGAUGUUUACGUAUAUUGGCAAACCAGUGAGUCGAAAACCGUGGUGACCUACCACAUCCCACAGAACAGCUCCUUGGAAAACGUGGACAGCCGCUACCGGAACCGAGCCCUGAUGUCACCGGCCGGCAUGCUGCGGGGCGACUUCUCCCUGCGCUUGUUCAACGUCACCCCCCAGGACGAGCAGAAGUUUCACUGCCUGGUGUUGAGCCAAUCCCUGGGAUUCCAGGAGGUUUUGAGCGUUGAGGUUACACUGCAUGUGGCAGCAAACUUCAGCGUGCCCGUCGUCAGCGCCCCCCACAGCCCCUCCCAGGAUGAGCUCACCUUCACGUGUACAUCCAUAAACGGCUACCCCAGGCCCAACGUGUACUGGAUCAAUAAGACGGACAACAGCCUGCUGGACCAGGCUCUGCAGAAUGACACCGUCUUCUUGAACAUGCGGGGCUUGUAUGACGUGGUCAGCGUGCUGAGGAUCGCACGGACCCCCAGCGUGAACAUUGGCUGCUGCAUAGAGAACGUGCUUCUGCAGCAGAACCUGACUGUCGGCAGCCAGACAGGAAAUGACAUCGGAGAGAGAGACAAGAUCACAGAGAAUCCAGUCAGUACCGGCGAGAAAAACGCGGCCACGUGGAGCAUCCUGGCUGUCCUGUGCCUGCUUGUGGUCGUGGCGGUGGCCAUAGGCUGGGUGUGCAGGGACCGAUGCCUCCAACACAGCUAUGCAGGUGCCUGGGCUGUGAGUCCGGAGACAGAGCUCACUGUUCCAGGAGCAACAUAGAUGUGGAUUCCUGUCCAAUUUGGGAAAAAUGUCCACACACGGUCACCCACCUGGCAGGUGCCUCUGGCUGCAAGGGGCGCUGGGCUUCGCAGGCAGGCCAGCCGGGCUCCCCGCCAUGGGCCAGGAUCCCCUCCGAGCCCUGUUUGCCGCCCAGGAGAAGGGGUUCCCCGGGGACAGUGGGCUCAGGGUGUGCGCAGCCACCAUGCUGUGGUGUCACCUGUGGACCCAGGCGAGCUGAUGGCCGACCGCAGAAACGCACUUCCAAGGCCAGGUCGGCCCAUCCAGAUGAUGCAGGAACACAGCUUGCUAAAAACACGGCCGGCCUGUUCCCGUCGGAGCCAGUCGAAGUUCCCUGAACAGGCCGCUGUUUCCGAAGCUUUAAACCCUGUGUUUCCACCAAGCUGAGUCCUGAGAAAACCGACGUCUGCCUGCAGAAGGGAAAGGGGUGCUUCAUGUUCCUCUCUCUCCUUCAUCUCCCUUCCAAGGCCACGUUUGACCGGAGCUCACCGCCCAGAGCGUGGACAGGGCUUCCGUGAGACGCCACCGUGAGAGGCCAGGUGGCAGCUUGAGCAUGGACUCCCAGACUGCAGGGGAGCACUUGGGGCAGCCCCCAGAAGGACCACUGCUGGAUCCCAGGGAGAACCUGCUGGCGUUGGCUGUGAUCCUGGAAUGAGGCCCUUUCAAAAGCGUCAUCCACACCAAAGGCAAAUGUCCCCAAGUGAGUGGGCUCCCCGCUGUCACUGCCAGUCACCCACAGGAAGGGACUGGUGAUGGGCUGUCUCUACCCGGAGCGUGCGGGAUUCAGCACCAGGCUCUUCCCAGUACCCCAGACCCACUGUGGGUCUUCCCGUGGGAUGCGGGAUCCUGAGACCGAAGGGUGUUUGGUUUAAAAAGAAGACUGGGCGUCCGCUCUUCCAGGACGGCCUCUGUGCUGCUGGGGUCACGCGAGGCUGUUUGCAGGGGACACGGUCACAGGAGCUCUUCUGCCCUGAACGCUCCCAACCUGCCUCCCGCCCGGAAGCCACAGGACCCACUCAUGUGUGUGCCCACAAGUGUAGUUAGCCGUCCACACCGAGGAGCCCCCGGAAGUCCCCACUGGGCUUCAGUGUCCUCUGCCACAUUCCCUGGGAGGAACAAUGUCCCUCGGCUGUUCCGGUGAAAAGUUGAGCCACCUUUGGAAGACGCACGGGUGGAGUUUGCCAGAAGAAAGGCUGUGCCAGGGCCGUGUUUGGCUACAGGGGCUGCCGGGGCUCUUGGCUCUGCAGCGAGAAAGACACAGCCCAGCAGGGCUGGAGACGCCCAUGUCCAGCAGGCGCAGGCCUGGCAACACGGUCCCCAGAGUCCUGAGCAGCAGUUAGGUGCAUGGAGAGGGUAUCACCUGGUGGCCACAGUCCCCCUUCUCACCUCAGCAAUGAUCCCCAAAGUGAGAGGUGGCUCCCCCGGCCCCCACCACCCUCAGCAGCCCCACCCCACUCAACCCUGAGGGUCCCCAGGGUCCUGAUGAAGACCUCCGACCCCAGCGCCAGGCUCCUCGGAGCCCAACAGUCCCAAGGGGGCAGGAGACGGGGUGGUCCAGUGCUGAGGGGUACAGCCCUGGGCCCUGACCAGCCCCGGCACCUGCCAUGCUGGUUCCCGGAAUGAAUCAGCUGCUGACUGUCUCCAGAAGGGCUGGAAAGGAUGCUGCCAGGUGACCCGAGGUGCACUCGCCCCAGGGAGAUGGAGUAGACAGCCUGGCCUGGCCCUCGGGACACAUUGUCUGCCCCGGGGCUAUGGGCAAAUGCCCCUCCUUCUUACUUCCCAGAAUCCCCUGACAUUCCCAGGGUCAGCCAGGACCUGUUACAGCCCUGGUCACUUGGAACUGACAGCUGUGUGAGGCCUGCACUUCUCAGACCCAGACUUAGAACAAAAGGAGGAGUGAGGACUCAAGGCUACAAUGAGGUUCCAGUACUUGUUACAAGAAAUUGGUUUUCUGCAAAAAAAGUCCCUACCUGAGCCUUUAGGUGAAUGUGGGAUCCACUCCCGCUUUUAACAUGAAAGCAUUAGAAGAUGUGUGGUGUUUAUAAAAGAACAGUUGUCAUCACCGGGCAUUGAUUGGCAGGGACAAGGAGCUGCUUGGGUGUGGAAAGUUGGGGCGUUGGAAAGUGGGCUGUGGUGCCCAUUUGCAGUGACUGUGAAGUGACUCCAGGACGGACCUGCGGGGGCACCCAGAGGUCCUAAGCCCCAGGACUGAGGGUCGUGCAUCACCACUCGGGUGUCCCGGGAGGUGCCCUGGGCCCGGGGACCUCACAGGCAGGACGGCGACACUAAUGCAGGGAGAGGGAGUCUGGCCCCAGCUUUUCCUAUCAGAGGCGAUUUUCCUUCACCAGGGGAUGGGCAGGAAAGAGGCAGGGGCCCCAGAAGCUUCUGUCCCUCAUGCCUGAGGGCACGGGGGACACUUGGAGGCUGCUGUCACCACUGUGCGUCCAAGGCCAUGCUCUCUGCGGGUCAGUGCCUGAGUCUCGCCUCCCUGCUGGUCCCUGAAGCCCCCUCAGAAGCCCUGCCUGUCACGUCGGCAUUUGUGAGACCUACCCUGUAACGCCUGCCCCUCUCAGCCCAACAUCAGCUUCCUCUUUCUCCCUUGCUGUAGACAGGCUGGAUUCCAGUGUUGGGACAGCCAUCUCCAGAAACCUGACUUAAGAGAGUAAGAUGCAAAUCGUGCCUGUAUCCAGUGGCUUUGGUGGGUGCAGGGAGUCUUGGGCACAGCCAGCUCAGCUGUCUGUGGUAUGAGCAGGAACAGGUGCCACUCCUGCUCAGGGGACCCUGCCCUACACCAGGCUGUUCCGUCCCCCUGGAGGACAUGGGGCCAGGUCUGGAGGCAUUUUGGGUUGUCACAGCUGGGGGCUGUUCCUCGGCUUCAGCGGGUGGAAGCCUCAGAUGCUGUUCAACAUCUUCUGGACACGGGAGGCCCCGACAGAGAGAAGCGUCCACCCGCAAGUCCACAGUCUGAGGUCUCCCCUCAGAGACCCUGCCCUGCACACCCACCUCCAGCCAAAGGUCCUGCCUGCCCCAGGGCUCAGGGGAACCUUGCCGGUCUGUGGAACAGGAGAGGGGACUCUCGCCAGCUGCACCACCCUGCACGUAGUAGGUGUGCGGUAAACAUCCACCAGGGAGGCUCCAGUCAAGGCUGGCAGAUGGGGCGGUCCAUCCCUAGGGCAGGUGACAGAAGGGAAAAGGCUGCCUGCUGGCCCCCGAGCCAGGUAGCACAUGCUUGUGCCUCAGUUUCCCCUCCUGUAAAGUGAGGCGCUGGAUCCAGGUUCUGUCUACUGGGCUCUGCAGCUUGGACGCUCCUAAGACCAAGCGACCCACCCUGGGGAGGGCAGCUAUGGCUUUGGAAUAGCUGUCCAGGCCCGGGUGCCUCCAAGACGGCCACCACACCCUGCCUGUGCUGCAGGGGUGCAGGGGUAAGGGGCAAGACUCCAGAGGCCUCCUCUCUGCAUCUCCUUGUCUUCAGUGGCCGGAGGUGAGGCCUGAGCUCAGGGGAGGGGCUUCUGCCACGAACCCUAUGGCGGGGCACAGCACACUUUUCCCAGGGAGGACCCCUGGGCCCCCUGCAUUAUCCCCAGCGGAGUGUGGGGUCACCUUCCAAGAGCGACAUUGAGAAGCUCCAGCUCUAGGAGUGUGCAGACUCUUAACCAGGCAGGCCCAGGCCCUGGGGCACACAAAGGCGGGGCCUGCUCUCCCCAGCUGCCCCUGCCAAUGGGGGCUGGACUGUCCUACCCUCCUCCCUUCUACCUCCCCACUGUCUUCCCUCUCCACUGUCACCACUGCCUCCCUCUUCCACUGUCCUCCAUGCACUGCCCUCCCUCCACCUUCCCCCACCCCCACCACUCCCCAUGCUGUCCCCAGGCUCCCCCCGCUCUCCCCCCUCCCCACUGUCCCCCUCCCCAUGCUGUACCCAGCUCACCCCGCUCUCCCCUCUCCCCACUGUCCCCCCUCCCACUCCCCAUGCUGUCCCCAGCUCACCCUACAUGGACUUGGCGAUGUCCUUCCAUGGCUCACCGGUCUGAAUUUCCAUGAUGAGCCGGGCCUGCAGCUUUGCUCCCCUAUCCCUGCCCAGGCUGCAGCUGUCCAUGCAGGGAGCGAGCUCCAGCACCUGCGGAGUCCUUCCGUGGGGGCCUCUCCGUGCCACAGCAGCCAGGGACCUCAGGUGCCUGUGCAUGACACCACCGCCCAUCCUCAUCCUGAGCCAGCCUCUCAGGAUCAGGACUUGGUUUGGCGGCGUUAACCUUAGAGCCUGCAAGGGGCUUCCUCCUGGUGGGUCUGGCCGUAGCCUGGGGAGGCCACAGCUCCAGGCCACUCCAGACCUCCCUUCCUCUGGGCCUUCCAUGUGGUGGCAACCACCGCAGCUGUAAGGGAGGGAAAAUGGAGCGUUUGUUCUCGGGCUGGGCUGGGGUCUGGGGGAAGCCAUGGGCGUGAAGACUGGAGUAUUAUUUGAUGGAGAAGCGGCCACUCCUGGAGACCGGCGGCAAACACAGAAGCACAGCGUGGAAGGUGCUGGUGUCAGCCCACACGGGUGAUGGGGUCAGACUCAGGAGUCACACUCAGGAGUCACCAGGCUCAAAGGGCCCAGGCACCGCAAGUCCUGCUCAGCCCCAGACACAAUGCAUUCCUGUUGCCCUCGCCCUCAGCCAGGCCCCACGCAGGCCAGGGAGCACUGGCAAAGCUUGGCAACCCUCUGGGGGCCAGCCUUCAUCCAGGCCGAAGGUGGUCAGUGGCCCACCAUGGCCCAGGUAGAAAACUCACGGAUUAAGAUUUCAUGCCCGACUCCAAAGGCAAGAGACUUUAUUAUUUUAUUUUUUUUGAGCCAGAGUAUCGCUCUGUCACCUAGGCUGGAGUGCAAUCUCUGCUCAUUGCAACAUCUGCCUCCCGAACUCAAGCAAUUCUGCCUCAGCCUCCCAAGUAGCUGGGAUUACAGGUGUGCGCCACCAUGCCCAGGUAAUUGUAUUUUUAGUAGAGACAGGGUUUCACCAUGUUGGUCAGGCUGGUUUCAAACUCCUGACCUCAAAUGAUCUGCCCACCUCGACCUCCCAAAGUGCUGGGAUUACAGGUGCGAGCCACCGCACCUGGCUACCAGACACUUCAGAGUUACAGGUUAGUUUUUCUUUUUCUUUUAUUUUUUUUUUUUUGGCGGAGGUGCAGGGGGAGUUAAACAAACAAACAAAAUAAACAGGCCGGGUGCGGUGGCUCAUGCCUGUAAUCCCAGCACUUUAGGAGGCCUAGGUGGGUGGAUCACGAGAUCAGGGGUUCAAGACCAGCCUGGCCGAGAUGGUAAAACCCCGUCUCCACUAAAAAUACAAAAAUUGGCCAGGCACGGUGGCUCACACCUGUAAUCCCAGUACUUUGGGAGGCUGAGGUGGGCAGAUCACCUGAGGUCAGGAGUUCAAGACCAACCUGACCAACAUGGAGAAACCCCAUCUCUACUAAAAAUACAAAAUUAGCCAGGUGUGGUGGUGCAUGCCUGUAAUUCCAGCUACUCGGGAGGCUGAGGCAGGAGAAUUGCUUGAACCCAGGAGGCAGAGGUUGCAGUGGGCCAAGAUGGCGCCAUUGCACUCCAGCCUGGGAACAAGAGCGAAACUCUGACUAAAAAAGAAAGAAAGAAAGAAAAAAAUUAGUUGGGCACGGUGGCAGGCGCCUGUAAUCCCAGGUACUCAGGAGGCUGAGGCAGGAGAAUUGCUUGAACCCGGGAGGCAGAGGUCGCAGUGAGCCGAGAUUGCACCACUGCCCUCCAGCCUGGGUGACAGAGCAAGACUCCGUCUCAAAAAAAAAAAAAAAAAAAAUUGGAUACAUUGUAAUACCUCAAAUACUUGUAAGUGAAGCACCCCAGUUCCCAUAGAGCUGCCGCACUCAGAGGCUUCUGUAACCUGCCUGCUCCCAGCAUUCUAUUUAGGGUCUGGUAUGUCCAGAAUUUGCAGACACAGCAAUUCCUGCAGCAGCAGUGCACCAUGUGGAAGGGGCCCCAUGACCAGCCCACUGUGAGCUCACACGUGAUGACUGAGGCUUCUUCACACAGCAGGGCUCUGGGUGUGAUACCCAGGGCACACGCGUUUGCACAGGCACAGGCCACACAAGUUCUCACAUGCUCAGCCCCAUAAGCCGUGCUGGACAGGCAUGGCCAUUUACACCCAGGAUCCUGCUGAGAACAGCAACCAACUCACCACCCUCGCAUCAUGAUCCUUGCCACACAGGGGCUCUGGUGGCUUUGGUGGCCUGGGCUGUGGCUCUGCUGCCAGCCACCUUGAGUGAAGAUCCGGGUUCUCUGGGUGCUACUCAGCUGCUAUGUGGGGAGCUGGCCCCUGGGGUGAUGAGGGCCCUUCCCAACCCGCCCUCAGCCCUUGGACAGCCAGGAUCACCCGGGGCUGUCUGCAUACAGACUUCUCAGGGGAGUUCUCAGCUUGGACCCUUAUCUCCCCAGAAUCCUGGAACCUGCUCCUUCUGCUCUCGUGACUGACUGUGUUCUCUAUGCAACUUCCAAUAAAACCUCUUCAUUUGAAAGGAAAAAA